AGUGCCCACAUGCUUCCAAGCCCGUGUGGCCUGUAGGAAGGCAGCCUAGCGUCCACAGGGAGAGAAGGCCUCCGAGUUCCUGCUGAACCACUCAACAGCUUAAAAUACAACCAGCCCCUCUCCCUGUCCAGCCAGCUGCUAGUGGGAGGGGUGAAAUCGUACCCUGCUCCCCCCAACCUGGGCACCAAACCAGGGCCCAAGAGGGAGAGUACGGCCAUCGGGGUCCCGGCUAGCUGCUGGGAGAGGACGCCGGGCUGCGGCAGGAGGGGGUAGCGAGAGAGGGGCCACGCUCACAGCUGCAGCAGUGGUGCCCAGGCCAGCCUGAGGCCCAAGGAGAGGAGACGCCCAAACCUGCAAGGAGGGCAGGAAGGCGCUGUCGGACCAGGAAGCUGGAAGGGGGCCAGAGGCUGAGCCCUGCAGAUACAAACUGACUGGAGGAGCAGGAGGAGCUCAUCCGGGCCAACCCCCGACUGCCCGAGUCCAGCAGACAGAUCCUGCCCCUGAGCUUUCAUGAGCUGUUGAACCAUCUGGAAUUCACAGGCCUGUCAUGAGAGACACGAUGAGAAGUCCUUAAAGGUAGAUCACUGAUUCACAGGGGAGCAGGCGGAGGCAAGGGCCUAAAGGGGAGUGGCCCCAGUGGCGGUAGCGGCGGUGGUGCCAAUGGUACCUCUUUCAGCUACACAUUCCAUGGAGACCCUCAUGCCAUGUUUGCUGAGUUCUUCGGUGGCAGAAAUCCCUUUGACACCUUUUUUGGGCAGCGGAACGGGGAGGAAGGCAUGGACAUUGAUGACCCAUUCUCUGGCUUCCCUAUGGGCAUGGGUGGCUUCACCAACGUGAACUUUGGCCGCUCCCGCUCUGCCCAAGAGCCCGCCCGAAAGAAGCAAGAUCCCCCAGUCACCCACGACCUUCGAGUCUCCCUUGAAGAGAUCUACAGCGGCUGUACCAAGAAGAUGAAAAUCUCCCACAAGCGGCUAAACCCCGACGGAAAGAGCAUUCGAAACGAAGACAAAAUAUUGACCAUCGAAGUGAAGAAGGGGUGGAAAGAAGGAACCAAAAUCACUUUCCCCAAGGAAGGAGACCAGACCUCCAACAACAUUCCAGCUGAUAUCGUCUUUGUUUUAAAGGACAAGCCCCACAAUAUCUUUAAGAGAGAUGGCUCUGAUGUCAUUUAUCCUGCCAGGAUCAGCCUCCGGGAGGCUCUGUGUGGCUGCACAGUGAACGUCCCCACUCUGGACGGCAGGACGAUACCCGUCGUAUUCAAAGAUGUUAUCAGGCCUGGCAUGCGGCGAAAAGUUCCUGGAGAAGGCCUCCCCCUCCCCAAAACACCCGAGAAACGUGGGGACCUCAUUAUUGAGUUUGAAGUGAUCUUCCCCGAAAGGAUUCCCCAGACAUCAAGAACCGUACUUGAGCAGGUUCUUCCAAUAUAGCUAUCUGAGCUCCCCAAGGACUGACCAGGGACCUUUCCAGAGCUCAAGGAUUUCUGGACCUUUCUACCAGUUGUGGACCAUGAGAGGGUGGGAGGGCCCAGGGAGGGCUUUCGUACUGCUGAAUGUUUUCCAGAGCAUAUAUUACAAUCUUUCAAAGUCGCACACUAGACUUCAGUGGUUUUUCGAGCUAUAGGGCAUCAGGUGGUGGGAACAGCAGGAAAAGGCAUUCCAGUCUGCCCCACUGGGUCUGGCAGCCCUCCCGGGAUGGGCCCACAUCCACCUCCAGUCCCUGGCCAGGGGUGAGAGGCAGACCAGCAGAUGGACUUGAUCCCUCUGUGUCUUUUUGCUUCUGGCUGGUAGAUAAUGUCAACCUGCAGUCUUGAUUCCCAGACCCUGUACACUCCUCCUUUUCUGUUGUGUGAUCAGUUUGUGCUUUAUUCUGUAUUUGUCUCCCAUGUCUUGCUCUUCUCCUGGAGAAUUCUGUCUUCUCUUUGGCCAUCUCAAAUUGAGAACCUAAACUAUUCCUGCAGAACUGCCUGGUUGGCGUCCACAAGCAAUACCUCUCGUUCCAGCAGGACCAAGGGAGCCAGCCUCCAGUGAGUGACUCCAGCAAGUGCAGCCACCUCUCCCUUGAUGGUCUGGGAGCCUGGCCUCAGCAAGGGGCCUUCCUGACCUCUGGCUCCAGUGAAGCUGAAUGUCCUCACUUUGUGGGUCACACUCUUUACAUUUCUGUAAGGCAAUCUUGGCACACGUGGGGCUUACCAGUGGCCCAGGUAAUUUUUUGUUUCAUGGACUAUGGACUCUUUCAAAGGGAUCUGAUCCUUUUGAAUUUUGCACAGCCCUAGAUACAAUCCCUUUUGAUAAAAGGGUCUUUGCUUCUGAUUACAGGAGCACUGUGGAACGUCUGUAAAUAUGUUUUUAUAAUUCCAUGUAUAGUUGGUGUACACUCAAAACCUGUCCCCGGCAGCCAGUGCUCUCUGUAUAGGGCCAUAAUGGAAUUCUGAAGAAAUCUUGGGGAGGGAAGGGGAGUUGGAACAAAUGUCUGUUCCCUGGAGGCCAGUCCAGUGCUCAGACCUUUAGACUCAUUGUAAGUUGCCACUGCCAACAUGAGACCAAAGUGUGUGACUAGUCAAUGAAGUGCGACAGCAUUAAAGACUGAUGCUAAACCUCA